GACCAGCCUGUAGUAACUGGCCCCUAGGCCGCAGUUCUUUGUCCUUAGCAGGAGGCCGUUUCUUGCCGGGAGAGAGGGAUUAGAGGGAUUGUCCGGCGUGGGUCUAGGGUCGUUGAGGCCUAAAGUUAAGCCUUUGUGGGGAGGACGGAUUGGGGGCUGGGUCACUUUAAGAAAAAGAUUCUAAAAUUACGAAGGCAGAAUUCCAGGGAGUCUCCCGGGCCUGGUCCUGAAGCUUGAGACCCCGGAUAUAUACGCUCCAGGGGGCUGCGGUGCGCUCUUCGGGUCCCCGAGCCCUGUGUUUAGGAACACGCGGGGACGUCCAAACACCCGCUCCUCUCCCGCCGGGCGGGCUCCUUUGUCUUCUGGGCUUUCGUCGCGAGAUGGAACGCUGGUUGAUGACGUUUUGAUUUUAAUAUGUUUGCUGCUGCUACCAAGAGCUUUGUCAAGCAAGUUGGAGAUGGAGGGAGAUUAGUUCCUGUUCCAAGCCUCAGUGAAGCUGACAAAUAUCAACCUCUAAGUCUGGUGGUAAAAAAGAAGCGAUGCUUUCUGUUUCCUAGAUAUAAAUUUACUUCAACACCUUUUACACUGAAAGAUAUUCUCCUAGGAGACAGAGAAAUUUCAGCUGGUAUUUCAUCUUAUCAAUUACUGAAUUAUGAAGAUGAAUCAGAUGUUUCACUCUAUGGAAGGCGAGGUAACCAUAUUGUAAAUGACGUUGGGAUUAACGUUGCUGGAUCAGAUUCCAUUGCAGUGAAAGCUUCAUUUGGUAUAGUAACCAAACAUGAAGUGGAAGUAUCAACAUUACUCAAAGAAAUUACUACACGAAAAAUUAACUUUGACCACAGCUUGAUACGUCAGUCAAGGAGCAGCAGAAAGGCAGUAUUGUGUGUGGUCAUGGAGAGCAUCCGAACCACACGACAGUGCUCACUGUCUGUGCAUGCUGGAAUUCGAGGGGAAGCAAUGCGGUUUCACUUUAUGGAUGAACAGAAUCCCAAGGGAAGGGACAAAGCUAUUGUUUUCCCAGCACAUACAACCAUAGCUUUCAGUGUUUUUGAACUCUUCAUAUACCUGGAUGGUGCCUUUGACCUUUGUGUCACUUCAGUGUCAAAAGGAGGAUUUGAAAGGGAAGAAACGGCAACAUUUGCACUGCUGUACAGGUUGAGAAAUAUCCUAUUUGAAAGAAAUAGAAGAGUGAUGGAUGUCAUUUCUCGUUCACAGCUUUACUUGGAUGAUCUUUUUUCUGACUACUAUGACAAACCUCUCAGCAUGACUGAUAUUUCACUCAAAGAAGGGACCCAUAUCCGAGUUAACUUACUUAAUCACAACAUUCCCAAAGGGCCUUGCAUACUCUGUGGAAUGGGGAACUUCAAAAGGGAGACAGUUUAUGGGUGCUUUCAGUGUUCUGUUGAUGGUCAGAAGUAUGUGAGACUUCAUGCAGUUCCUUGUUUUGAUAUUUGGCACAAGAGGAUGAAAUAAAAUGAAAAAUGAAUACACCGUGUUGGUGUUUUAGGUGCAGUUGUGCCACAAACCUUCCCUAAAUUAUCUAGGUUUGCUUUGAUGAAUUAAAUUAAAAUGAGAAAAGCAAAAAGAAAUUAACCUGUCUGGGUAUCAUAUUCCCUAUCUAUAAAGUAGCAAUUAUAACAGUAGUGUCUAUUUCUUAAGUUGUCAUGAAAAUUAAUAACAUUGUUUAUAUCAAAAAAGAUUUACAUAUAAAAUUCAGAGAUUAUGAAUCAUGCCAGUCACUUUAGAAUCAUUUUUGGGAUGUAGUCUAUCAUUUUAGUUCACCUUUUUUUUUUUUUUUUUUGAGACAGAGCCUUGCUCCGUCACCCAGGCUGGAGUACAGUGGCAUGAUCUCAGCUCACUGCAACCUCUGCCUCCUGGGUUCAAGCAAUUCUCUGCCUCAGCCUCCCGAGUAGCUGGGAUUACUGGCGCCUGCCACCACGCCUGGCUAAUUUUUUGUAUUUUUAGUAGAGACAGAGUUUUACCAUCUUGGCCAGGCUGAUCUUGAACUCCUGACCUUGUGAUCCACUUUCCUCGGCCUCCCAAAGUGCUGGGAUUACAGGCAUGGGCCACCGUGCCUGGCCUAGAUAACUUUUUAUAUAAUUAAGAGAUUUUUGUAAAUACCAAUUUUAUUUUCAAUCAACUUUCAGUUCAAUAUGUAAGGAUGACAAGACUGCACAAGUAGCAACUUUUGGUGUUUCAACUAUUGCCUUUGGUCUGGUAAAAUGAGAAAAAUGUGUUAAUAAUUUAAUGCAAUCUUAAAUGUUUAAUUGCAGUAUCAAAUUAAAAGCACACUGAACUCAA